AUUUGACUCACUGACCCUGAUGGGGAAGAUAGUGUUAUUCCCACAGUGUGGUAGUACACACUGGGGCUUAUAGGGACUGAGCCUACUCAAGGGUAUAUGGUGCUGUGGGUCAGAGCUGGGGCAUGGCCCAGGGAUUCAGUGUGCCUUGACUCCCCCUGUAAAUGUUCCUCUCAGAAGCCUUCUUGGCCUUCCAGCCCUUGGUUUUUGAGACAACCAGCAGUCAUUUGUUCGUUCCUGACAUUCCUUCCUGUCCCUUCCUUCCAGGUUCUGUGGACAAUCACAAUGGGAAUCCAAGGAGGGUCUGUCCUGUUCGGGCUGCUGCUCGUCCUGGCUGUCUUCUGCCAUUCAGGUCAUAGCCUGCAGUGCUACAACUGUCCUAACCCAACUGCUGACUGCAAAACAGCCGUCAAUUGUUCAUCUGAUUUUGAUGCGUGUCUCAUUACCAAAGCUGGGUUACAAGUGUAUAACAAGUGUUGGAAGUUUGAGCAUUGCAAUUUCAACGACGUCACAACCCGCUUGAGGGAAAAUGAGCUAACGUACUACUGCUGCAAGAAGGACCUGUGUAACUUUAACGAACAGCUUGAAAAUGGUGGGACAUCCUUAUCAGAGAAAACAGUUCUUCUGCUGGUGACUCCAUUUCUGGCAGCAGCCUGGAGCCUUCAUCCCUAAGUCAACACCAGGAGAGCUUCUCCCAAACUCCCCGUUCCUGCGUAGUCCGCUUUCUCUUGCUGCCACAUUCUAAAGGCUUGAUAUUUUCCAAAUGGAUCCUGUUGGGAAAGAAUAAAAUUAGCUUGAGCAACCUGGCUAAGAUAGAGGGGCUCUGGGAGACUUUGAAGACCAGUCCUGUUUGCAGGGAAGCCCCACUUGAAGGAAGAAGUCUAAGAGUGAAGUAGGUGUGACUUGAACUAGAUUGCAUGCUUCCUCCUUUGCUCUUGGGAAGACCAGCUUUGCAGUGACAGCUUGAGUGGGUUCUCUGCAGCCCUCAGAUUAUUUUUCCUCUGGCUCCUUGGAUGUAGUCAGUUAGCAUCAUUAGUACAUCUUUGGAGGGUGGGGCAGGAGUAUAUGAGCAUCCUCUCUCACAUGGAACGCUUUCAUAAACUUCAGGGAUCCCGUGUUGCCAUGGAGGCAUGCCAAAUGUUCCAUAUGUGGGUGUCAGUCAGGGACAACAAGAUCCUUAAUGCAGAGCUAGAGGACUUCUGGCAGGGAAGUGGGGAAGUGUUCCAGAUAGCAGGGCAUGAAAACUUAGAGAGGUACAAGUGGCUGAAAAUCGAGUUUUUCCUCUGUCUUUAAAUUUUAUAUGGGCUUUGUUAUCUUCCACUGGAAAAGUGUAAUAGCAUACAUCAAUGGUGUGUUAAAGCUAUUUCCUUGCCUUUUUUUUAUUGGAAUGGUAGGAUAUCUUGGCUUUGCCACACACAGUUACAGAGUGAACACUCUACUACAUGUGACUGGCAGUAUUAAGUGUGCUUAUUUUAAAUGUUACUGGUAGAAAGGCAGUUCAGGUAUGUGUGUAUAUAGUAUGAAUGCAGUGGGGACACCCUUUGUGGUUACAGUUUGAGACUUCCAAAGGUCAUCCUUAAUAACAACAGAUCUGCAGGGGUAUGUUUUACCAUCUGCAUCCAGCCUCCUGCUAACUCCUAGCUGACUCAGCAUAGAUUGUAUAAAAUACCUUUGUAACGGCUCUUAGCACACUCACAGAUGUUUGAGGCUUUCAGAAGCUCUUCUAAAAAAUGAUACACACCUUUCACAAGGGCAAACUUUUUCCUUUUCCCUGUGUAUUCUAGUGAAUGAAUCUCAAGAUUCAGUAGACCUAAUGACAUUUGUAUUUUAUGAUCUUGGCUGUAUUUAAUGGCAUAGGCUGACUUUUGCAGAUGGAGGAAUUUCUUGAUUAAUGUUGAAAAAAAACCCUUGAUUAUACUCUGUUGGACAAACCGAGUGCAAUGAAUGAUGCUUUUCUGAAAAUGAAAUAUAACAAGUGGGUGAAUGUGGUUAUGGCCGAAAAGGAUAUGCAGUAUGCUUAAUGGUAGCAACUGAAAGAAGACAUCCUGAGCAGUGCCAGCUUUCUUCUGUUGAUGCCGUUCCCUGAACAUAGGAAAAUAGAAACUUGCUUAUCAAAACUUAGCAUUACCUUGGUGCUCUGUGUUCUCUGUUAGCUCAGUGUCUUUCCUUACAUCAAUAGGUUUUUUUUUUUUUUUUUGGCCUGAGGAAGUACUGACCAUGCCCACAGCCACCGGCUGAGCAAAGAAGCUCAUUUCAUGUGAGUUCUAAGGAAUGAGAAACAAUUUUGAUGAAUUUAAGCAGAAAAUGAAUUUCUGGGAACUUUUUUGGGGGCGGGGGGGUGGGGAAUUCAGCCACACUCCAGAAAGCCAGGAGUCGACAGUUUUGGAAGCCUCUCUCAGGAUUGAGAUUCUAGGAUGAGAUUGGCUUACUGCUAUCUUGUGUCAUGUACCCACUUUUUGGCCAGACUACACUGGGAAGAAGGUAGUCCUCUAAAGCAAAAUCUGAGUGCCACUAAAUGGGGAGAUGGGGCUGUUAAGCUGUCCAAAUCAACAAGGGUCAUAUAAAUGGCCUUAAACUUUGGGGUUGCUUUCUGCAAAAAGUUGCUGUGACUCAUGCCAUAGACAAGGUUGAGUGCCUGGACCCAAAGGCAAUACUGUAAUGUAAAGACAUUUAUAGUACUAGGCAAACAGCACCCCAGGUACUCCAGGCCCUCCUGGCUGGAGAGGGCUGUGGCAAUAGAAAAUUAGUGCCAACUGCAGUGAGUCAGCCUAGGUUAAAUAGAGAGUGUAAGAGUGCUGGACAGGAACCUCCACCCUCAUGUCACAUUUCUUCAAUGUGACCCUUCUGGCCCCUCUCCUCCUGACAGCGGAACAAUGACUGCCCCGAUAGGUGAGGCUGGAGGAAGAAUCAGUCCUGUCCUUGGCAAGCUCUUCACUAUGACAGUAAAGGCUCUCUGCCUGCUGCCAAGGCCUGUGACUUUCUAACCUGGCCUCACGCUGGGUAAGCUUAAGGUAGAGGUGCAGGAUUAGCAAGCCCACCUGGCUACCAGGCCGACAGCUACAUCCUCCAACUGACCCUGAUCAACGAAGAGGGAUUCAUGUGUCUGUCUCAGUUGGUUCCAAAUGAAACCAGGGAGCAGGGGAGUUAGGAAUCGAACACCAGUCAUGCCUACUGGCUCUCUGCUCGAGAGCCAAUACCCUGUGCCCUCCACUCAUCUGGAUUUACAGGAACUGUCAUAGUGUUCAGUAUUGGGUGGUGAUAAGCCCAUUGGAUUGUCCCCUUGGGGGGAUGAGCUAGGGGUGCAAGGAACACCUGAUGAGUAGAUAAGUGGAGCUCAUGGUAUUUCCUGAAAGAUGCUAAUCUAUUUGCCAAACUUGGUCUUGAAUGUACUGGGGGCUUCAAGGUAUGGGUAUAUUUUUCUUGUGUCCUUGCAGUUAGCCCCCAUGUCUUAUGUGUGUCCUGAAAAAAUAAGAGCCUGCCCAAGACUUUGGGCCUCUUGACAGAAUUAACCACUUUUAUACAUCUGAGUUCUCUUGGUAAGUUCUUUAGCAGUGUUCAAAGUCUACUAGCUCGCAUUAGUUUCUGUUGCUGCCAACAGAUCUGAACUAAUGCUAACAGAUCCCCCUGAGGGAUUCUUGAUGGGCUGAGCAGCUGGCUGGAGCUAGUACUGACUGACAUUCAUUGUGAUGAGGGCAGCUUUCUGGUACAGGAUUCUAAGCUCUAUGUUUUAUAUACAUUUUCAUCUGUACUUGCACCUCACUUUACACAAGAGGAAACUAUGCAAAGUUAGCUGGAUCGCUCAAGGUCACUUAGGUAAGUUGGCAAGUCCAUGCUUCCCACUCAGCUCCUCAGGUCAGCAAGUCUACUUCUCUGCCUAUUUUGUAUACUCUCUUUAAUAUGUGCCUAGCUUUGGAAAGUCUAGAAUGGGUCCCUGGUGCCUUUUUACUUUGAAGAAAUCAGUUUCUGCCUCUUUUUGGAAAAGAAAACAAAGUGCAAUUGUUUUUUACUGGAAAGUUACCCAAUAGCAUGAGGUGAACAGGACGUAGUUAGGCCUUCCUGUAAACAGAAAAUCAUAUCAAAACACUAUCUUCCCAUCUGUUUCUCAAUGCCUGCUACUUCUUGUAGAUAUUUCAUUUCAGGAGAGCAGCAGUUAAACCCGUGGAUUUUGUAGUUAGGAACCUGGGUUCAAACCCUCUUCCACUAAUUGGCUAUGUCUCUGGACAAGUUUUUUUUUUUUUUUUUUUUUAAACCCUUUCUGAACUUUCACUUUCUAUGUCUACCUCAAAGAAUUGUUGUGAGGCUUGAGAUAAUGCAUUUGUAAAGGGUCUGCCAGAUAGGAAGAUGCUAGUUAUGGAUUUACAAGGUUGUUAAGGCUGUAAGAGUCUAAAACCUACAGUGAAUCACAAUGCAUUUACCCCCACUGACUUGGACAUAAGUGAAAACUAGCCAGAAGUCUCUUUUUCAAAUUACUUACAGGUUAUUCAAUAUAAAAUUUUUGUAAUGGAUAAUCUUAUUUAUCUAAACUAAAGCUUCCUGUUUAUACACACUCCUGUUAUUCUGGGAUAAGAUAAAUGACCACAGUACCUUAAUUUCUAGGUGGGUGCCUGUGAUGGUUCAUUGUAGGUAAGGACAUUUUCUCUUUUUCAGCAGCUGUGUAGGUCCAGAGCCUCUGGGAGAGGAGGGGGGUAGCAUGCACCCAGCAGGGGACUGAACUGGGAAACUCAAGGUUCUUUUUACUGUGGGGUAGUGAGCUGCCUUUCUGUGAUCGGUUUCCCUAGGGAUGUUGCUGUUCCCCUCCUUGCUAUUCGCAGCUACAUACAACGUGGCCAACCCCAGUAGGCUGAUCCUAUAUAUGAUCAGUGCUGGUGCUGACUCUCAAUAGCCCCACCCAAGCUGGCUAUAGGUUUACAGAUACAUUAAUUAGGCAACCUAAAAUAUUGAUGCUGGUGUUGGUGUGACAUAAUGCUAUGGCCAGAACUGAAACUUAGAGUUAUAAUUCAUGUAUUAGGGUUCUCCAGAGGGACAGAAUUAGUAGGAUAUAUGUAUAUAUGAAAGGGAGGUUAUUAGGGAGAACUGGCUCCCACAGUUAGAAGGCGAAGUCGCACAAUAGGCCGUCUGCAAGCUGGGUUAGAGAGAAGCCAGUAGUGGCUCAGCCUGAGUUCAAAAACCUCAAAACUGGGGAAGCUGACAGUGCAGCCAGCCUUCAGUCUGUGGCCAAAGGCCCAAGAGCCCCUGGCAACCAACCCACUGGUGCAAGUCCUAGAUUCCAAAGGCUGAAGAACCUGGAGUCUGAUGUCCAAGAGCAGGAAGAGUGGAAGAAAGCCAGAAGACUCAGCAAACAAGGUAGACAGUGUCUACCACCAUAGUGGCCAUACCAAAGAGGCUACCGAUUCCUUCCUGCUACCUGGAUCCCUGAAGUUGCCCUGGUCUCUGCACCUUCUAAACCUAGUUCUUAAGAGCUUUCCAUUACAUGAGCUGUCUCAAAGCCCUCCAAUAAAUUCUCAGUGUAAGCUUCUGUUGCUUGUGGACAGAAAAUUCUGACAGACCUACCCUAUAAGUGUUACUGUCAGGAUAACAUGAGAACGCACAACAGUAAGUGGUCACUAAGUGUUAGCUACGGUUAUUUUGCCCAAGGUAGCAUGGCUAGUUGAUGCCGGUUGAUGGGGCUUAAACCCAGCUCCCUCAUCUUCCAGGCCUCUGUACUCCCUAUUCCACUAAACUACCUCUCAGGUUUAUUUUUUUAAAUUCUUACUCUGCAAGUACAUAGGACCACAUUUACCUGGGAAAACAAGAAUAAAGGCUGCUCUGCAUUUUUUAGAAACUUUUUUGAAAGGGAGAUGGGAAUGCCUGCACCCCCAAGUCCAGACCAACACAAUGGUUAAUUGAGAUGAAUAAUAAAGGAAAGACUGUUCUGGGCUUCCCAGAAUAGCUUGGUCCUUAAAUUGUGGCACAAACAACCUCCUGUCAGAGCCAGCCUCCUGCCAGGAAGAGGGGUAGGAGACUAGAGGCCGUGUGUGCAGCCUUGCCCUGAAGGCUAGGGUGACAAUUUGGAGGCUGUCCAAACACCCUGGCCUCUAGAGCUGGCCUGUCUAUUUGAAAUGCCGGCUCUGAUGCUAAUCGGCGACCCUCAGGCAAGUUACUUAACCUUACAUGCCUCAGUUUUCUCAUCUGGAAAAUGAGAACCCUAGGUUUAGGGUUGUUAGAAAAGUUAAAUGAGUUAAGACAAGUGCCUGGGACACAGUAGCCUCUUGUGUGUGUUUAUCAUUAUGUCCUCAGCAGGUCGUAGAAGCAGCUUCUCAGGUGUGAGGCUGGCGCGAUUAUCUGGAGUGGGUUGGGUUUUCUAGGAUGGACCCCCUGCUGCAUUUUCCUCAUUCAUCCACCAGGGCUUAAUGGGGAAUCAAGGAAUCCAUGUGUAACUGUAUAAUAACUGUAGCCACACUCCAAUGACCACCUACUAGUUGUCCCUGGCACUGCUUAUACAUAUGUCCAUCAAAUCAAUCCUAUGAAGUAGAUACUGUCUUCAUUUUAUAGAUCAGAGACAAUUGGGGUUCAGAGAGCUGAUGUGAUUUUCCCAGGGUCACAGAGAGUCCCAGAUUCAGGCACAACUCUUGUAUUCCAAGACACAACCACUACAUGUCCAAAGGCUGCCCAGAGCCACCGGGCACGGCAAAUUGUGACAUAUCCCUAAAGAGGCUGAGCACCUGGUCAGGAUCUGAUGGCUGACAGUGUGUCCAGAUGCAGAGCUGGAGUGGGGGAGGGGAAGGGGGGCUCCUUGGGACAGAGAAGGCUUUCUGUGCUUUCUCUGAAGGGAGCAGUCUGAGGACCAAGGGAACCCGGCAAACAGCACCUCAGGUACUCCAGGCCCUCCUGGCUGGAGAGGGCUGUGGCAAUGGAAAAUUAGUGCCAACUGCAAUGAGUCAGCCUCGGUUAAAUAGAGAGUGAAGAAUGCUGGACAGGAACCUCCACCCUCAUGUCACAUUUCUUCAGUGUGACCCUUCUGGCCCCUCUCCUCCUGACAGCGGAACAAUGACUGCCCCGAUAGGUGAGGCUGGAGGAAGAAUCAGUCCUGUCCUUGGCAAGCUCUUCACUAUGACAGUAAAGGCUCUCUGCCUGCUGCCAAGGCCUGUGACUUUCUAACCUGGCCUCACGCUGGGUAAGCUUAAGGUAGAGGUGCAGGAUUAGCAAGCCCACCUGGCUACCAGGCCGACAGCUACAUCUUUCAACUGACCCUGAUCAACGAAGAGGGACUUGUGUCUCUCAGUUGGUUCCAAAUGAAACCAGGGAGCAGGGGCGUUAGGAAGCUCCAACAGGAUGGUACUUAAUGGGGCAUUUGAGUGGAGAGGUAGGUGACAUAGUGCUUUGGAGCCCAGGGAGGGAAAGGUUCUGCUGAAGUUGAAUUCAAGACUGUUCUUUCAUCACAAACUUGAGUUUCCUGGACAUUUGUUUGCAGAAACAACCGUAGGGUUUUGCCUUAACCUCGUGGGUUUAUUAUUACCUCAUAGGGACUUUGCCUCCUGACAGCAGUUUAUGGGUGUUCAUUGUGGCACUUGAGUUUUCUUGCAUACUUGUUAGAGAAACCAAGUUUGUCAUCAACUUCUUAUUUAACCCCCUGGCUAUAACUUCAUGGAUUAUGUUAUAAUUAAGCCAUCCAGAGUAAAAUCUGUUUAGAUUAUCUUGGAGUAAGGGGGAAAAAAUCUGUAAUUUUUUCUCCUCAACUAGAUAUAUACAUAAAAAAUGAUUGUAUUGCUUCAUUUAAAAAAUAUAACGCAAAAUCUCUUUUCCUUCUAA